AUGUGCAUCCCCGCCUCCCGCUCCAGGCGAGUCCUUCCCUGGACUCCAGUCCCUUGUGGGAAACAAUCCCUCGCCUCCGGAGGCGGCGAGGAGCGGCGGGUGAGCCCCGGAGCACUGGGCGAGGGCCAGGGGGUCCCCGCGCUGCCCUGAAGGCGGGCGGGCGGCGGCUAGACCUCGGCGGUGGGGAGGGACCCCUGGCGCCUGCGGCGACGGUGGGACGAGGGCGUCUCUGUCAGAAGGGGAUGAGGUCUGGCGUGGGAACGCGAGUUCCGGGGCUCCCGGGGGUCCGUAUGCGUCCAGUCCCUGCGCCUGGCGCUCAGCGAAGUCCUGUAGCACGGGGUAGGCAAUGCGCACUGGCCCGAAGGGGAGGGAACUGGCUGCGGGGAGGGGACAGCACGCGCGUGCGUAGCGUGUGACGUUUGUUGUGCGCGUGCGCAUGGCGUUUGAUGUGUGCGUGUGCGCUUUUUGUGCCCUGAGCCCGCGGGGAGGAGGCGGGGCUGCGGGGGAGAGCGACUGCGCCAGGUCCGCGACAAAUGAAUUAGACACAAUUAUCCACGGGAGACUCGGUUUUCCUCUCUGUAAAUUACGGAUAUUAGGAAUACUUGCCGCCUGGGGUUGUUUUGAGCACUUUCAUUGUUUAGGUGCUGUAUUUAUUGGGUGUGCGUUCCCUGGGAGAGCCCGAGGGAGACGGCUCCUGCACCGGCCCCAAGGGCCUCUCUGCCCGUGGAGUGCAGGAGCGAAGGGGCUGGCCUAGCUGACCACCAGGGCCCCUGCUGGCUCUGACCGCCCUCCUAUCCCAAGUAAUUAUUUACACGUUUCGCGUUCGCUUAUGUAUUAUGUGUAAUCAUGGCACAGUAUCCUGAAGCCGUCGGAGUCUGUGUGCUGGUGCAAGGUCUGGGACAAAUUUAAGAAGAGAGAGGUGAGCUGGAGCUGAGGGGUGGGCGCGCAGGCUAACAGGAACGUCACCUCUGGAGAGUCUGAGGGCAGGGACGGGUGAAAGGCUCACGGCCACAGCGAAAGAAAUGCUGUUAUCACCCCUCCGCGAACACCGGGCACAUCCAGAUGAGCUGCUGAGCUUCCUCCUCUCUUGGCCUGAUAUCCCCGCCGGAUGGUAGUGCAGUCAGGUCAUACUUGGGUUAUCUGUUUUGACCUUAUUUGAAAGAUGGAAAAACAAAAUUGAGUUUGAGGAGGUGAGUAGUUCAGAUCUUGUCAUUCCUUAGAGGCAGAACUGAGAUUAGAAGUCAAGUCUGCAGUUUCCCGAGCCACUGCUGCCCAUUUUGUUACUCUAUAUCACAGUUUCUCAUUAAAAGAUCCUUUUGAGGAAUUGUUAGCAAGUUAGAACAAACAUUUUUAAACUUGCAUUUAACAUCCUAUCCCUUUUUUUAGAGGUCUUUUGCAUUAUCUAACCUCAGGGCAUUAAUGGUGUUAACAGGUAAACAGAUAAACAAUAUGGCCUCAGUUUUUUUUUUUCCCUACAAGGAAUUUUGACAAACCCAUAGUGUUUUUUCCUUCAGAUUACUGUUAACUUGUUAAACUCAUCUUUUCAUGUUUUUAAUUUUUCUGUGUCACAGAACCUAAAUUGGUAAUAAAUCAAUAAGAAAUAUUUACAUUCACUCAGUGAAAAGUGUCAUGUCUGAGCUCAGCAUAUAUCGGAGCCACACAUGGACACCUCUCCUUCCUCCACUAAGAGCGGAAAAUGAACAAAUCCCAGGAACAAGUGUCAUUCAAGGAUGUAUGUGUGGACUUCACUCAGGAAGAGUGGUAUCUGCUGGACCCUGCUCAGAAGAUUCUAUACAGAGAUGUGAUCCUGGAAAAUUAUAGCAAUCUUGUCUCAGUAGGGUAUUGCAUUACUAAACCAGAAGUGAUCUUUAAGAUCGAGCAAGGAGAAGAGCCCUGGAUAUUAGAAAAAGGAUUCCCAAGCCAGUGCCACCCAGAAAGGAAAUGGAAAGUUGAUGACGUGUUAGAGAGCAGCCAGGAAAAUGAAGAUGACCAUUUUUGGGAGCUUCUAUUCCACAACAACAAAACAGUAAGUGUAGAAAAUGGAGAUAGAGGAAGCAAAACUUUCAAUUUGGGCACAGACCCUGUUUCUUUAAGAAAUUAUCCCUAUAAAAUAUGUGACUCAUGUGAAAUGAAUUUGAAAAAUAUUUCGGGCUUAAUUAUUAGUAAAAAGAACUGUUCCAGAAAGAAGCCUGAUGAGUUUAAUGUAUGUGAGAAAUUGCUCCUUGAUAUUAGGCAUGAGAAAAUCCCUAUUGGAGAGAAGUCUUAUAAAUAUGAUCAAAAAAGGAAUGCCAUUAAUUAUCACCAGGAUCUCAGUCAGCCAAGUUUUGGCCAAUCUUUUGAGUAUAGUAAAAAUGGACAAGGCUUCCAUGAUGAGGCAGCAUUUUUUACAAAUAAGAGAUCUCAGAUAGGAGAGACAGUCUGUAAAUAUAACGAAUGUGGAAGAACCUUCAUUGAAAGUUUAAAGCUGAAUAUAUCUCAAAGACCUCAUUUGGAAAUGGAGCCGUAUGGAUGCAGUAUUUGCGGGAAGUCCUUCUGCAUGAAUUUAAGGUUUGGACAUCAGAGAGCUCUUACAAAGGACAAUCCUUAUGAAUAUAAUGAAUAUGGGGAAAUCUUCUGUGACAAUUCAGCUUUCAUUAUCCAUCAGGGAGCUUACACAAGAAAGAUUCUCCGUGAAUAUAAAGUGAGUGACAAAACCUGGGAAAAGUCAGCUCUCUUAAAACAUCAAAUAGUACACAUGGGGGGAAAGUCUUAUGAUUACAAUGAAAAUGGGAGUAAUUUCAGCAAGAAGUCACAUCUUACCCAGCUUCGGAGAGCUCACACAGGAGAAAAAACCUUUGAAUGUGGUGAAUGUGGGAAAACCUUCUGGGAGAAGUCAAACCUCACUCAACAUCAGAGAACACACACAGGAGAGAAGCCCUAUGAAUGUACUGAAUGUGGGAAAGCCUUUUGCCAGAAACCACACCUGACCAACCAUCAGCGAACACAUACAGGAGAAAAACCCUAUGAAUGUAAGCAAUGUGGAAAAACAUUCUGUGUGAAGUCAAACCUCACUGAACAUCAGAGAACACACACAGGGGAGAAGCCCUAUGAAUGUAAUGCAUGUGGGAAAUCCUUCUGCCACAGAUCAGCCCUCACUGUGCAUCAGAGAACACACACAGGGGAGAAACCGUUUAUAUGUAAUGAAUGUGGAAAAUCCUUCUGUGUGAAGUCAAACCUCAUUGUACAUCAAAGAACUCACACUGGGGAGAAACCAUAUAAGUGUAAUGAAUGUGGGAAAACCUUCUGUGAAAAAUCAGCUCUCACUAAACAUCAGAGGACUCACACAGGGGAGAAGCCGUAUGAGUGUAAUGCAUGUGGGAAGACCUUUAGUCAGAGGUCAGUGCUCACCAAACAUCAGAGAAUUCACACAAGGGUGAAAGCUCUUUCAACAUCCUGAAUGUUAGAAGCCUUCAUACACUUGUGAAAUUGGUUAUACAGUUUCAAAAAAGGAGAUCAGAGAAAGCCAAAGAAUGUCAGAAAUUUGUAGAAAAUGACUUCUUGUUUGAAUAUGUAAAAGCUUUCAAGAAAAAUUAAAACUUUUCAUUAGAAAAUUUGUACUGAGGGGAAUUCUAUUCAUCUAAGUAAUAUGGUGAAAAUAUUUAUCUGGAAUUUAUGUUGUUUAGUGUUAUAUUCCAGACGUGAUACCAAAAUUUUGUUGCAAAUAUAAUGGACAAUAUUUAUUUAUACCCAUAUUCACAGUGGAAUCUGAAGCUUAUAAAAGUUGAAUGACAGCAGCAUUAAACAUAUAUGUGAAGAGUCCCCGAUGUUUGUAGACCUUAUGUGAGUAUGCAAAUAUAUAAAUUUGAGUAUGCUUGAUUUGUAUAUUGGAACUCAACAUGAUCAUAAGGAGAAGAUACGUACCCUUAAUUGAGUAACUACUAUGGUAUUUGUUAAUAUUUUCUACACUAAAUACCAUUGGUGUCUUUAUAGGUUGACAUAAUUAUAUAUGUGUAUGUACAUAUGUUUGUGUGUAUAUGUAAAUAUAUUUCUACACACAUACUUAAAUAUAGUGAUGUGCUAGUAUAACCUCAUACUGACUUAAAAGUUCUGAUUGUUAAAUUUUAAGGAAUUUUGUGAGCCAGUUAUUAAAAGCAGUCAUUAUUUAAAAUAUGUAAACUUACAGUUAAAAACAAAGGUAAUAAAUACUCAGCACUCAUCACUUCCUAAUUAUUUUGCUACAUUUCACUAUUACCUUUGCUGUUUUACUUAUUUAAUCUGUAUGAUGAAAAUACUGUAUAAUAGUGUGCACUGCACAUCUGUCUCUUCCCAGCUCCACAUUCAGUGCUGUCUUGGUAGCUUGGACUUAGUGGGAGUGUUUACACCAUGGAAAUUGACAAACUAUAAAUCAGGGUUUUAAUUUUCUCAGAGAACCUGCUGUCAAAUAUUUACAGCACAUCACUGUGUAUAUAUGAAAACGUAUUUGGCAAUACAAACCACAUACCCCUUCUAUUUCCUGACAUAAAUAAAUGGCUAUGGCCAUUUACAGCUGAACCACGUCUUCAAGAAAGAAGCCAAAAAUAUUUCCGUGAGGUUUUUAACUACCUCUGAAUCUGUCCUACUCUAAAUACUACCGGAGUCUCUUUGUAGGUUGGCCAGUAUAUGUUUUUAGUGAAAUAUUAUUUCACAAAGAACUAUAUCACGUACCUUUCCUCUGACUGUUUCCUGGCAUAUAUGCAUGAAUAUGGCCAUUAUUGAACUAUCACUUCAGUAAAGAAGUUAAACAGUACUUUUCUGAGGUUUUUCAGCUACCUCUGGGUCAUUCUGUAAUGUAAAUGUUGUUAAUAAGAAUGGUUUUUACAUAAAUUAUGCAAAGGUUAACAAGCAGUAACACUGCACUCCUCAAAAAGUGGCGGUAUGUAAUGAAAGGCCCUUUUGAUAUCCUUGAUUUUUCAUUGUGUAUCUGUUUGGGCACGGUCUAUGUAACACUAGUUCUGCGUAUUAGUAUUUUAGAGUAUCUCUGCCUCCCUUGUCCUGUUGUUUCUUUUGCCCCCUUGGAACACAUUGGUCAGCAGUUCUAAGAGACACUGCCCACAUGAUGGCCAUUCCCUACUUCAUCCUUGCUGAGCUAAAUUUUAUAUUUUUGUGCAUCCUUCUCCCAGAUGACUUAGGUGGUAAGUCCAGAUUAGUCAAAGCUAAUCAUGGAAGUUCCAUUUUAAUGAUUCUGUUGGGGUGAACUUGGGAGCAAUGAGAUGUUUGGGAAGUAUUGUGUAGUACUUCUGGGAAAGAUCUCCUUGAUACAACAUUGUCAUGACAUGAGAAGAGACUCUGCUGGGCUUUUUCAUGUCUGUAACAUGGUAUUGGCUUAUCGUUUUUAUCUCUGAAGGGCAGUAGCCUGAAGAUAACAGUGCACAAGGUGGGAAAAGCCAGCUCAGAGGUGACGUUGCCGAGCUACUCUGCUCUCUAUACCUGUUCUCUACUGGGACUUUUUAUAACCCUCAAUAACUGUUUUUUAUUUGGUCUUAGGGCUGUCUGAUACUUAGAGCUGAAGGCAUUCCAGCUGACACAGAGGAAUAUUUUUCUAAGUGUUAAUGUUCUAUAUGGUAAUUAGGGGGAAGAAUUAUUUCUUUUCACAAGUUAAUAUAGGGAUGGCUGUUUGUAUCAGCCAUGGUUCUUUCUGGUGGAAAACAGAAUUCUCCAACUAAAAAUAUUUUAAUGGCAGACUGAUUACAGUGGUGUGGGCCAGAAACAAGGGACAGUGAAACACCCAGAGACUUGUAUCAGCAGGAAGCCAUUGCCAUUCUGAGCCUUGAAGGGCAAGGAGGGAAACAGUGUUACCAGAGCCCAGUAAGAACUGCUGUCAUGAAGGAGGGGCCACCUUGUAAGAGACAUCAUUACUACCAGAACUGUGGUGCCAAAUUGCUGGUGUCUCUCUUUGGAGAAACCAACCAGAUACAUCUGCUGGAGAGCCCAGGUGGGCACAGAGAAGGGUGGAGAGAGAAUCUGGGAAGAGAAAUGGAGAAUAAGCAGCACAGUGUUAUUCAUUUCUGUAAAUUCCUAUGUAGAAGGCUCAGUGUUAGAAAUAAAGUUAUUCUACUAGUUGCAAGUUAAGUGUUUCUGUUUGUUCUGCUUUCCUGUUAGCAUAAGUAAACUCCCUUUGGAACUACACAGGUAUGUCUCUCCUUCAACAUGUGUGAAGCAGACAUUAUAUUAAAUUACAUUAUUCAUACCUCCCUGUGGUGUUUCUUAUUGUAUGUGGUGUAAGGUAAGCAGCUCUGUAUUCUUCCAAAUAAAUAGCCAGUUGUCCCUGCA